UUAUUUCACUGUACUAUUAAAAAUAAUUUAAACUUCUCUCUCUCUCAGACCAGAAUGAGAGCUUCUACAGGAUGAAAAUAUCUCCUAAUUCAUCUUGGACUCAUAAGUAUUGAGUAUUGGCCUGAACCGAGUAGGACUCCUGGAAUCUCAUCAUCAUCCUGGAACAUUAGAGGUGGAAGGGGUCUUCAGGAUUACCUGGAAACCUCUGUCUGCAGUGAAAAAUUUAGUCAGUCCAGCACAGGGGUCUUAUGUAGAUACACUCCAAAGGACUCUGAAGAAGGCAUUGGUUAUCCUCCAGGUAUCCAUCUUAAAGGCUCAUCUAAUCGUCAACUACAGGAUUCAAAGAUGUAUAAGAUAAUUCUGGCCGGGCACAGUGGCUCACGUCUGUAAUCCCAGCACUUUGGGAGGCCGAGGUCAGUGAACAAUUUCCUGAUAACAGGUCCCAAGGCCUAUCUGACCUACACGACUAGUGUGGCCUUGGGUGCCCAGAGUGGCAUCGAGGAGUGCAAGUUCCAGUUUGCUUGGGAACGCUGGAACUGCCCUGAAAAUGCUCUUCAGCUCUCCACCCACAACAGGCUGAGAAGUGCUACCAGAGAGACUUCCUUCAUACAUGCUAUCAGCUCUGCUGGAGUCAUGUACAUCAUCACCAAGAACUGUAGCAUGGGUGACUUCGAAAACUGUGGCUGUGAUGGGUCAAACAAUGGAAAAACAGGAGGCCAUGGCUGGAUCUGGGGAGGCUGCAGCGACAAUGUGGAAUUUGGGGAAAGGAUCUCCAAACUCUUUGUGGACAGUUUGGAGAAGGGGAAGGAUGCCAGAGCCCUGAUGAAUCUUCACAACAACAGGGCCGGCAGACUGGCAGUGAGAGCCACCAUGAAAAGGACAUGCAAAUGUCAUGGCAUCUCUGGGAGCUGCAGCAUACAGACAUGCUGGCUGCAGCUGGCUGAAUUCCGGGAGAUGGGAGACUACCUAAAGGCCAAGUAUGACCAGGCGCUGAAAAUUGAAAUGGAUAAGCGGCAGCUGAGAGCUGGGAACAGCGCCGAGGGCCACUGGGUGCCCGCUGAGGCCUUCCUUCCUAGCGCAGAGGCGGAACUGAUCUUUUUAGAGGAAUCACCAGAUUACUGUACCUGCAAUUCCAGCCUGGGCAUCUAUGGCACAGAGGGUCGUGAGUGCCUACAGAACAGCCACAACACAUCCAGGUGGGAGCGACGUAGCUGUGGGCGCCUGUGCACUGAGUGUGGGCUGCAGGUGGAAGAGAGGAAAACUGAGGUCAUAAGCAGCUGUAACUGCAAAUUCCAGUGGUGCUGUACGGUCAAGUGUGACCAGUGUAGGCAUGUGGUGAGCAAGUAUUACUGCGCACGCUCCCCAGGCAGUGCCCAGUCCCUGGGUAAGGGCAGUGCCUGAUAAUACCCCACACAAGUUCACUUGAUUAAUUGCAUCAGUGGAAGGGGACAUAGCUUCUCUCUUAGAGAGAACAGAUUGGAAAGCAAUCGGAAAAUUGCAGUUUUGGUCUGUAGUCCUCAUGAUAUCUGCUAUCAGUGGGGAAAAUGGAGGCCCAAGAUUCUACAGCAUAUUCCUGGCGGGGCUGAAAUUGGAACCUGGGCCUCCUGACUUUGGCAGACCCCCAUUUCAUCUUUCCUGCAAACUACUUUCCCAUCUUUGUGCCUGUACUUAUGCAGCUUUCUACAGGGAGAGUUUGGUUUGGGGUCUAUAUCUAGAGGGACCUUCAAAGUAUUUGUUCCUUUAAAUUUCAGACCAUGUCCAACCCAGCUGUGCUGCUGGGAAUCAGGAGAAUAGAAGCAAAAAACGAAAGAGUUCUGUUCAGACUUCUGAAGAGCAGCCUGUGGCUACAAAUCUAUGCUGAUAAAUGAG